AAUCAGAGAAAAUGAGAAGCCAUGAGGCCUUUGGGAGAAUCUUAGGAAAAAAUUCUCUCUCAUCCCCUUGGGAUUCAAAGCUGAGAAGAUGUAAGGACUGGAGCUGCAGCAGUCUUUCUGGGACCAUUAUACAGAGAUUCUGUCUGAGGUUGGAUCCACGUGGUCAAAAGUAUUGCUGAGGAGCCAGAGAGAGACUGAGGUCUGAUGACAUCACUUGAGCCCUGCAGACUUUUCAUUUACGGGAAAACAGAGAGGAUGAAGGCCUAUCUAAAGAGCGCAGAAGGCUUUUUUGUCCUAAAUAAAAGUACCACAAUUGGAAGGCAUGAAAAUUCAGACCUUGUUUUACAGUCUCCUGACAUCGACAACCACCAUGCACUCAUUGAAUAUAACGAGGCGGAGUGCAGCUUUGUUCUCCAGGACUUCAAUUCCCGCAACGGCACGUUUGUCAACGAGUGCCACAUUCAAAACGUGGCUGUGAAGCUCAUCCCUGGAGACAUCCUGAGAUUUGGGUCUGCAGGGCUGACCUAUGAACUGGUCAUUGAAAAUCCACCUCCGGUCUCUUUCCCAUGGAUGAGGGGCCCAGCACCAUGGCCAGGGCCACAGCCACCUCGUGCCACACAGCAGCCAAACCAGGCCCCCCCACCAUCACAUAUCCCCUUCCACCAAGGUGUCCAGCCAGCACCGAUGCAAAGGAGCUGGUCCCAGGCCUUUCCCAGACCCACCGUGGUCCUGCCGGCCUCCCACAGGCGGCCUGUGAGCGCCAACAAGGAGAUGUUCUCGUUCGUGGUGGACGACGCCCGCAAGCCACCCGUCAUCAAGCAAGUGUGGACCAAUGCCAUGAAACUGUCAGAAAAAUCAGUGGCCGAGGGGAUUCCUGGGGCAGUUCCCCCUGCGGAGAUUUAUGUGGAGGAGGACUUGGCCCAGCAGGACAAGGAUGAAAUAAUUCUGCUGCUGGGAAAAGAGGUCAGCCGUCUCUCAGAUUAUGAAAUUGAAUCCAAAUACAAAGACGUCAUAAUAGCAAACCUGCAGAAUGAAGUGGCUGAGCUGAGUCAGAAGGUGUCAGAGACCACCACCUCCAGGCAGAAUGAGAAGGAGAUCUCGCAGAAGUGUCAGGUUCUGGAUGAAGACAUCGAUGCCAAACAGAAAGAGAUCCAGAGCUUGAAAAGCCAGAUCAGUGCCCUACAGAAAGGCUACAGCAAGGUGCUGUGCCAGACCCUGUCAGAGCGGAACUCAGAAAUCACAUCCCUGAAGAAUGAGGGCGAGAACUUAAAGAGAGACAACGCUAUCACAUCAGGGAUGGUGUCAUCUUUGCAAAAAGACAUAUUAGCAAAGGAUGAGCAAGUUCAACAACUAAAGGAAGAGGUCAGUCACCUAAAAAGUCAGAACAAGGACAAGGACCACCAGCUGGAAGCCCUUGGCUCUAGAUGCUCGGUGCUAAAGGAAGAGUUAAAACAGGAAGAUGCUCACAGGGAGCUCAGGGAAGCCCAGGAGAAAGAGUUAAAACUCUGCAAAACCCAAAUCCAAGACAUGGAGAAAGAAAUGAAGAAGCUUAGGGCAGAGCUGAGGAAGAGUUGUACUGAACAAAGCGUGAUCUCUAGGACUCUGAGAGAAAAAAGCAAGGUUGAAGAGAAGCUUCAGGAGGAUUCCAGAAGGAAAUUGCUUCAGCUGCAAGAAAUGGGGAACAGAGAGAGCGUCAUUAAAAUCAAUUUGGAGAGGGCAGUAGGUCAGCUGGAGCACUUCAGAAGUCAAGUCAUCAAGGCCACCUAUGGACGGGCGAAGCCGUUCCGGGACAAGCCCGUCACCGACCAACAGUUAAUAGAGAAAAUUACCCAGGUCACUGAGGACAACAUCAAUUUUCAGCAGAAAAAGUGGACCCUCCAGAAAGAGACCCAGCUGAGCAACUCCAAGCAGGAGGAGACCACCGAGAACAUCGAGAAGCUGAGGACGUCGCUGGACAGCUGCCAGGCUUGCAUGAAAAUAUCCUGUUGCAGCCAUGACCUGAAGAAGGAGGUCGACCUUCUUCAGCACCUCCAGGUGAGCCCACCUGUCUCGGGGCUCCAGAAGGUGGUGCUGGACGUCCUGAGGCACGCGCUGUCCUGGCUGGAGGAGGUGGAGCAGCUCCUCCGGGACCUCGGGAUCCUGCCCUCCAGCCCCAACAAAGGGUUCUCUUUGUAUCUGAUAUAUCUUCUGGAACAUUAUAAAAAACUUAUGAGCCAGGCCCAGGAACUUCAGAUCAAGUUCAACAGUUCUCAGGAAACUCAGCAGUCUUUACUGCAGGAAAAGCUGCGGGAGCAUCUGGCAGAGAAGGAGAAGCUGAACGAGGAGAGGCUAGAGCAAGAGGAGAAGCUCAAAGCCAAAAUCAGGCAACUGACGGAAGAGAAGGCGGCUUUGGAGGAGUACAUUACUCAAGAGAGAAACAGAGCGAAAGAGACUUUAGAGGAAGAACGGAAGAGAAUGCAAGAACUGGAGAGCCUCCUGGCCCAGCAGAAGAAGGCUUUGGCGAAAAGCAUUACCCAGGAGAAGAACAGAGUGAAGGAAGCAUUAGAGGAAGAGCAGACAAGAGUCCAAGAGCUGGAGGAACGCUUGGCCCGCCAGAAGGAGGUUUUGGAGAGCAGCAUAGCCCAUGAAAAAAGAAAAGCAAAGGAAGCCUUGGAGUCGGAAAAGAGAAAAGUUCAGGAUCUGGAGAACCAUUUAACCCAACAGAAGGAGAUCUCAGAGAGCAACAUUGCGUACGAGAAACGCAAAGCAAAGGAGGCCAUGGAGAAGGAAAAGAAAAAGGUGCAAGACCUGGAGAAUCGCUUAACCAAGCAGAAAGAGGAAUUAGAAUUAAAAGAGCAAAAAGAGGACGUUUUAAAUAAUAAAUUAAGUGACGCACUGGCCAUGGUUGAAGAGACUCAGAAAACAAAGGCAACUGAAAGUCUAAAAGCAGAGAGCCUCGCCUUGAAAUUAAAUGAAACAUUAGCCGAACUGGAAACUACCAAGACAAAAAUGAUCAUGGUGGAAGAGCGGCUAAUCCUGCAGCAGAAGAUGGUAAAGGCCCUCCAGGAUGAGCAGGAAUCACAGAGACACGGGUUUGAAGAAGAGAUCAUGGAAUAUAAGGAGCAAAUCAAACAGCACGCCCAGACAAUUGUGAGCCUCGAAGAGAAACUCCAGAAAGUCACUCAGCACCAUAAAAAAAUAGAAGGCGAGAUUGCAACAUUGAAGGACAAUGACCCAGCCCCAAAGGAGGAAAGGCCGCAAGACCCUCUGGUGGCUCCCAUGACAGAGAGCAGUGCCAAAGACAUGGCGUACGAACAUCUGAUAGAUGACUUAUUGGCUGCUCAGAAGGAAAUUCUGUCUCAGCAGGAAGUCAUCAUGAAGUUAAGGAAAGACCUUACCGAAGCCCACAGCAGAAUGUCGGAUUUGAGAGGGGAGCUAAACGAGAAGCAGAAGAUGGAACUGGAGCAGAACGUGGUGCUGGUCCAGCAGCAGAGCAAGGAGCUGAGUGUGCUCAAGGAGAAGAUGGCCCAGAUGAGCAGCCUGGUAGAAAAGAAAGAUCGGGAGCUGAAGGCCCUUGAGGAGGCACUCAGGGCUUCCCAAGAGAAACACAGACUCCAGCUGAACACAGAGAAGGAACAGAAGCCCCGGAAGAAGACCCAGACGUGUGACACCUCUGUGCAGAUAGAACCCGUCCACACUGAGGCCUUCUCCAGCAGCCAAGAGCAGCAAUCCUUCAGCGAUCUAGGGGUCAGGUGCAAAGGGUCCCGGCACGAGGAGGUCAUUCAGCGUCAGAAAAAGGCCUUAUCUGAACUUCGAGCGCGAAUUAAAGAACUCGAGAAGGCGCGCUCACCAGAUCAUAAAGACCACCAGAAUGAAUCAUUUCUAGAUUUAAAGAACCUCAGAAUGGAAAACAAUGUCCAGAAAAUACUACUGGAUGCAAAACCGGAUUUGCCAACUCUCUCAAGAAUAGAGAUCCUAGCGCCUCAGAAUGGCCUUUGCAACGCAAGGUUCGGCUCAGCCAUGGAGAAGUCAGGGAAGAUGGAUGUGGCUGAGGCUUUAGAGCUCAGUGAAAAGCUGUACCUGGAUAUGAGCAAAACCCUCGGAAGUCUCAUGAACAUCAAGAAUAUGUCAGGCCACGUGUCCAUGAAAUACCUCUCCCGCCAGGAGAGGGAGAAGGUCAACCAGCUUCGACAAAGGGACCUCGACCUGGUGUUUGAUAAGAUCACCCAACUCAAGAACCAGCUGGGGAGGAAAGAGGAGCUGUUGAGAGGAUAUGAAAAGGACGUUGAACAGCUCAGGCGGAGCAAAGUGUCCAUUGAGAUGUACCAGUCGCAGGUGGCAAAGCUGGAGGAUGAUAUCUACAAAGAGGCCGAAGAGAAGGCCCUGCUGAAGGAGGCCCUGGAGCGCAUGGAGCACCAGCUGUGCCAGGAGAAGAGGAUCAACAGGGCCAUCCGGCAGCAGAAGGAAAGUGUAGAGGAGCACGAACUGAGAAACGCAAAAGAAUCGACACCUUGCAACUGUGCCUUCAAAGAGAAAGACAGGCAGAGACGAGUAUUUGUAGAGAUGGUGAAGAACAGGAUGCAGAACUCAAAUUCCCAGGUUGGAACCAGAAAAGCCUCCCUAAAGAUGGACCAAGAAAGAGAGAUGCUGAGGAAAGAGACCUCCAGCAAGUCCAGCCAGAGCCUUUUGCAUUCUAAGCCCAGUGGAAAGUACUAGAGAAACCUCGUCCCACCAGGCCUCAUGUGAUCCUCUCAGGCCCACUCAUCCUUCAGCCGACUGGACUAGGCUCGUUCACAUGUGGUGGCCACAGGUUGCCAAGAACAGCAGGUGAGAACAAGCCCCAGUGCACAAGCACUUUUCAAGUUUCUACUUGCCUUAUGUUUGUUAAUAUCCCAUCAGAUAAAGCCAGAGUCUGUGUGGGAGGAGCUCCAGAUUUUUACAAUCUACUCACAUUGGGUUUUCUGCUAUUUGAAGCUGAAUACAUUCCCAGCUGACCCAGAAGAAAGUUACCUUGAUUCCCAAUGACUUUCUGAUUCCCAGUUCCCUUCCUUGUGAAGGCCAGUUCCAGUACCUGCCCUUGGGUUCCACUAGGACCCUUUGUAUCACUCAAGAUCCCUUGGUUGUAAACAACAGAUACCUCCUGUGGCUAACUUAAACAGAAAGAGAGUUUACUGGGAGGAAAUGAGGAAGGUCAGAGAAUCAGUGGCUAUGCAAAGCUGAAGAGUCAGGCUUGGACAUCAGGAGCUGGCUUUUCUUCCCUAUAGGUGCCCUCUUUUUGCUUUAGCUGGUUUGAGUUUCUGUUCAUUGCAACCAAAUGGGCAUUUACUACGACGCUCUGCUACACAGCCCCCACCCACUACUGAUUCUGAGAAGCUACCAGCAGUCUUUCCCCUGGGGGUUGCACCACAGUACAGUGAGGUACCUGUAUACCCAAACCUCCCAAUCUUCUUCUGAUCUUUCAAGAAGCUAAGACACACAACUUCCUUCCGCCCUUGCCAGUGGGAGCCCAUGUGGAUCCUUGGAUUCGUGACUUUGCAGAUAAGGUGCCCUUCUCUUGAAACUUGGCAGCAUCACCAUCGCCUGCUGUUGUAGAAACCAAAGUCAUGAAAUGUCUGGAGGGAAAAAAUAGCUUCCAGAUCUGCAUUCCAAAGUGUGCUCCUGGUAAGUGGAGUGGUUUCCAAUUUUUUAGGGACUUAGGAAUGAAGGCAAUCCACUAAGGAUGUGAGGAAACCUAAACCUAAUAACGCUAAUGCAUGCCUCUUUGCCAUGCUGAGGCCUCCUAAAGCAGGAUGGAGGGCACCAGUGAGGCUAUUUCAGCUCAUCAGCUUGGCCUCAUUUCCGUCAGGUGCACUGCUUGCAUCCGUCUGCUCAGUGUCCCAGGUUAUUUUGGGCCAAUUCAUGACCUUAUGUGCCUGCUUUUGUUUUUAAACAUUUUUCUUUGCCCAUCUGUUGCCCAGGAAUCCUUUUGCAAUGCCUCCGUCCAGUUGGGGGAAGCAUUAACAGGUCCUUGUUUUGAGUUUCCUGUCAUCUUUAGCAAACUGUUUUCCUUUCUAAGACCCAAAAAUAUUGGAGGCAGAAACUUUAUCUUCUGGCUAACUGUGGUCUUAUCAUCAGAGAGUAUGGUUUGACAGUUAAACAACCAGCCUCCAUCCAUUCAGCCGGUAGACACUGGGGGCCUACUAUGGGCCAGGCUCUGAUGCUACCGUGUUAGUUAGACCUCAUGGCCUUGACCUUUACUCCUUUUCAAAUUCUGAUCCACUGCUUUAACUGAAAAGGAAGUUGGAAUCAUUAAUUUACUGGGUAUGUUGCAUAGGAGCACUUACUUUUUUUUAAAAUUUUUUUAUUAUUAUACUUUAAGUUUUAGGGUACAUGUGCACAACGUGCAGGUUUGUUACAUGUGUAUAUAUGUGCCAUGUUGGUGUGCUGCACCCAAGGAGCACUUACUUUUGACGUCCACAUAUCUUGUUGGCUACGUAUGGGAUUGCUGCUGGGCGUUCUUUAAAGACAGCGGCAUGCAGCAAUGACCCGCUUCCUGGGAGUUUCUUUGUACCUUUCAUCAGUUGAAAUAUAAUAGCUAAUAAUAGUAACUACUUUGUAUAGAGUACUUCCUAGCCAUGAGACACUAUGCAAAGCGUGGUCCAGACAAUAUCCCACUUCAUCCCCACCAUGUCAUUACUCCUGUUAUACCUGUGAAAAUGAUGAGCCCAGACUAGGUAAGUAACUUGCCCAAGGUCACAGAGCAAGUGUUGGAGCCCAGACUUUAUACCCACAACUGCUUAAUAUAGCACUUUCCUCAAGGAAGUCCAGGAACCAGCUGGUUGUCUACUAAUGAAUGAGGGCAGGAUGACAGACUUUUUCUGUAAAGGGCCGAAUAGUAAAUCCUUUCUUCUGUAAAGGACUCUAUUGACCAUAGGUGUCUUAUCACCACCACUCAACUCUAGCAGAGCAGCAUGAUAUGUAAAUGAAUGAGCAUGGCCAUGUUUCAAUAAAACUUUAUUUAUAAAAAUA